AGUGAAAGCCCGAGCGGCGGCGGCGGCGGGGACGGCGGUGGAGGCGGCCGGGUGGCUGUGCGCGCGUGUGGGGCGCAGGCUCGGCGGCAGCGGCCGGUCUGGAGCGGCCGCUGCGAGGAAGACAGCUGCAGCGGGGGAGGCGCGGCCAGGGCUGCGCGCUCCGCGGAGCCGGCGGGGCCGGGAACAGGUGAUCCCAGUGGGAGCCCCGCGCCCUGCCGAGUUCGAGGGGCGGGAGCCCGCGCUCCCGGGCGCAUCUGCAGCCGCCCAGCCGCGGCUCCGGACCCAGGCAUCCCUGCGCUGUCUGGGGCCCGGGGGAAGCCCCCUGCCCCCGCAGGCUCGGAAGUGCCUGCUCCUGCUCCCUGGCCACUCCGGCUCCCAGCUCCCGGCGCCCUCUCCGCGGCGGAGAAAGUUGUGGACGUGUCCCGAUAGUCGAGCCCGGGCGCUGUCGCGACCGGGCCGGGUGUGCGCGCGCUCGGGGCGGCGCUGACACGCCAGCCCCCCAUCGCCUCGGUCCCCUCCGGAAACUGCUUCUGAAGCUGAAACUUUGGGCGCCUACCAGCGCGGGCGGGAGCCUAGGGGGCGGAGGGCGGCUUGGUGCGGGCCUGCGGGCGCCCCUCGGCGCGGACAGCCGGGACGCCGCGGACGGCAUGUGACGGUCCCGGCGGCCGCAGCGCGGGAAGGCGCGGGCCCCGGCGCGGCGGGGAGGGCUCGGCCGGAGGGGAGGCUGCGGCGCGCGGCCGGUCGCUGCGGGCCCGGGCCCCAAGCCGUGCCGCUCCGCUCGCCCGGGCCCCGCCGAGGCCGCUGCGCCCCCGCCUCCUCGCGGGAGGACUCGCUCCAAACUCCCUGAACUUCGGGGACAGUCCCCCGAAGCGGCGAAACUCUCAGGGUUGGCAACCCUGCCCAGGGACCCCCAUCCCGGGCGGCGCUCCGGACGCCCUCCCCUCACCGCGCCCCCGCAGACACGUGCCUGGACUCCGAGGGCUUCUGGAGCCACCGGCCGGGCCACGAUGCUCAUGAGGAAAGUGCCCGGCUUCGUCCCGGCCUCCCCGUGGGGGCUGCGGCUGCCGCAGAAGUUCCUCUUCCUCCUCUUCCUCUCGGGCCUGGUCACCCUGUGCUUCGGGGCCCUCUUCCUGCUGCCCCACUCCUCUCGCCUCAAGCGCCUCUUCCUGGCCCCCCGGACCCAGCAGCCUGGUCUGGAAGUGGUGGCUGAAAUCGCCGGCCAUGCCCCGGCCCGCGAGCAGGAGCCGCCUCCCAACCCGGCCCCCGCCGCGCCGGCCCCGGGCGAGGAUGACCCCAGCAGCUGGGCCAGUCCCCGCCGCAGGAAAGGGGGGCUGCGGCGCACCCGCCCCACUGGACCCCGCGAGGAGGCCACGGCGGCCCGGGGCAAUAGCAUCCCGGCCUCCAGGCCCGGGGACGAGGGCGUCCCUUUCCGCUUUGACUUCAACGCAUUCCGGAGCCGUCUCCGCCACCCGGUCCUGGGAACGAGGGCCGAUGAGAGUCAGGAGCCCCAGAGCCAAGUGCGAGCCCAGCGGGAGAAAAUCAAGGAGAUGAUGCAGUUUGCUUGGCAGAGCUAUAAGCGUUAUGCAAUGGGGAAAAACGAACUCCGUCCACUAACAAAAGAUGGCUACGAGGGUAACAUGUUCGGAGCCAACCCCUCAGGAGAAGACAGAGUGGCUGGGAAAGCAGAUCCGUGCGUGAUGCCCCUGGUGAUGAAGGCUGGGGAAAACCAGAGAAGACAAGGAGACAGAGGCCUCAGCGGGGCAACAGUCAUUGACUCCCUCGAUACCCUCUACCUCAUGGAGCUGAAGGAGGAGUUCCAGGAGGCCAAGGCCUGGGUGGGAGAGAGCUUCCACCUGAACGUGAGCGGAGAAGCAUCCUUGUUUGAGGUGAACAUCCGCUACAUCGGGGGACUCCUCUCAGCCUUCUACCUGACAGGAGAAGAGGUGUUCCGAAUAAAGGCCAUCAGGCUGGGAGAGAAGCUCCUGCCGGCGUUCAACACCCCCACGGGAAUCCCAAAGGGCGUGGUGAGCUUCAAAAGUGGGAACUGGGGCUGGGCCACAGCCGGCAGCAGCAGCAUCUUGGCGGAGUUUGGAUCCCUGCACUUGGAAUUCUUACACCUCACUGAACUCUCUGGCAACCAGGUCUUCGCUGAAAAGGUCAGGAACAUCCGCAAGGUCCUCAGGAAGAUCGAAAAGCCCUUUGGCCUCUACCCCAACUUCCUCAGCCCAGUGAGUGGGAACUGGGUGCAACACCAUGUCUCAGUUGGAGGACUCGGGGACAGUUUUUAUGAAUAUUUGAUCAAAUCCUGGUUGAUGUCGGGCAAGACAGAUAUGGAGGCUAAAAAUAUGUACUACGAAGCCUUGGAGGCGAUAGAGACCUACUUGCUGAAUGUCUCUCCCGGGGGGCUGACCUACAUUGCCGAGUGGCGAGGGGGGAUUCUGGACCACAAGAUGGGGCACCUGGCCUGUUUCUCCGGGGGCAUGAUCGCCCUUGGCGCCGAGGAUGCCAAGGAAGAAAAGAGGGCCCACUACCGAGAGCUCGCAGCCCAGAUCACCAAGACGUGUCACGAGUCAUACGCCCGCUCAGACACCAAACUUGGGCCUGAGGCCUUCUGGUUUAACUCCGGCAGAGAGGCCGUGGCCACCCAGCUGAGCGAGAGCUACUACAUCCUCCGGCCAGAGGUGGUGGAGAGCUACAUGUACCUGUGGCGACAGACCCACAACCCCAUCUACAGGGAGUGGGGCUGGGAGGUGGUGCUGGCCUUGGAGAAAUACUGUCGGACAGAAGCCGGUUUCUCUGGGAUCCAAGACGUGUACAGUAGCACCCCCAACCACGACAACAAGCAGCAGAGCUUCUUUCUAGCGGAGACACUAAAGUAUCUCUAUCUUCUGUUCUCUGAAGAUGACUUGCUCUCCCUGGAAGACUGGGUGUUCAACACCGAGGCCCACCCACUCCCGGUGAACCACUCAGACAGCUCCGGCAGAGCCUGGGGCAGACACUGACCCCAUCUCCUGCCGCCGCCCUGGGGCCGCCGCAGGGAUGCCUUGCCUUUUCAGGAUUUGAGACUGUUCUCAAAGGGAUUGGGAACGAAGGCCCCAUCUCGGGCAGACCCCCAGCAGAUGUGUCGGACAAGCAACUUCUUUUCCUCUGUGAGGAGACAAGACUUGGAGACUCAGCGAUGUCAGGCCAGGGCCAUGGCCACACUGGCCCACACAUUCCUUUCUACAGAGAAUUUCUAUGAAGCCCACUCACUUGCCAUUCCAGGGCCAAAGGACCGGAGGUUUGCAUAUCCGCCCCUUGUAUUUGAUUUGCUUCCUUUUGGUUUCUUGGUUUUUGUUUUUGCUUGAUUUUGUCUUUUCUCUACAGUUUAGUUUUGUCACAAUUACACAUAUAGUUUUCAAAAUCAUGCACUUUCUAAAAUGGUGUCAUCCUGAAAAACAAAACCCAGUGUUUGCACACACACAAAAUCUUGACCCCGUUAUCUAUAUUUUAAAUGCUUUUUGCCCAACACUGACCCUAUGUUCAACUUUGUGUCAUUUACCUUAUAAUUUGAGGAGGGGUUUCCCUUUGGGCCUCAGUGUUACAAAUUACUAGUGCUAUUUUCAUUAUUAUUGUAAUGGAAAAAUCUGUGGACUAGAAUAAAAGAGUUUAUUGAAUAAGAAA